ACUUGCAGCGGGGGAGGCGGAGACGGCGGAGCGGGCCUUUUGGCGUCCACUGCGCGGCUGCACCCUGCCCCAUCCUGCCGGGAUCAUGGUCUGCGGCAGCCCGGGAGGGAUGCUGCUGCUGCGGGCCGGGCUGCUUGCCCUGGCUGCUCUCUGCCUGCUCCGGGUGCCCGGGGCUCGGGCUGCAGCCUGUGAGCCCGUCCGCAUCCCCCUGUGCAAGUCCCUGCCCUGGAACAUGACUAAGAUGCCCAACCACCUGCACCACAGCACUCAGGCCAACGCCAUCCUGGCCAUCGAGCAGUUCGAAGGUCUGCUGGGCACCCACUGCAGCCCCGAUCUGCUCUUCUUCCUCUGUGCCAUGUACGCGCCCAUCUGCACCAUUGACUUCCAGCACGAGCCCAUCAAGCCCUGUAAGUCUGUGUGCGAGCGGGCCCGGCAGGGCUGUGAGCCCAUACUCAUCAAGUACCGCCACUCGUGGCCGGAGAACCUGGCCUGCGAGGAGCUGCCAGUGUACGACAGGGGCGUGUGCAUCUCUCCCGAGGCCAUCGUUACUGCGGACGGAGCUGAUUUUCCUAUGGAUUCUAGUAACGGAAACUGUAGAGGGGCAAGCAGUGAACGCUGUAAAUGUAAGCCUAUUAGAGCUACACAGAAGACCUAUUUCCGGAACAAUUACAACUAUGUCAUUCGGGCUAAAGUUAAAGAGAUAAAGACUAAGUGCCAUGAUGUGACUGCAGUAGUGGAGGUGAAGGAGAUUCUAAAGUCCUCUCUGGUAAACAUUCCACGGGACACUGUCAACCUCUAUACCAGCUCUGGCUGCCUCUGCCCUCCACUUAAUGUUAAUGAGGAAUAUAUCAUCAUGGGCUAUGAAGAUGAGGAACGUUCCAGAUUACUCUUGGUGGAAGGCUCUAUAGCUGAGAAGUGGAAGGAUCGACUCGGUAAAAAAGUUAAGCGCUGGGAUAUGAAGCUUCGUCAUCUUGGACUCAGUAAAAGUGAUUCUAGCAAUAGUGAUUCCACUCAGAGUCAGAAGUCUGGCAGGAACUCGAACCCCCGGCAAGCACGCAACUAAAUCCCGAAAUACAAAAAGUAACACAGUGGACUUCCUAUUAAGACUUACUUGCAUUGCUGGACUAGCAAAGGAAAAUUGCACUAUUGCACAUCAUAUUCUAUUGUUUACUAUAAAAAUCAUGUGAUAACUGAUUAUUACUUCUGUUUCUCUUUUGGUUUCUGCUUCUCUCUUCUCUCAACCCCUUUGUAAUGGUUUGGGGGCAGACUCUUAAGUAUAUUGUGAGUUUUCUAUUUCACUAAUCAUGAGAAAAACUGUUCUUUUGCAAUAAUAAUAAAUUAAACAUGCUGUUACCAGAGCCUCUUUGCUGGAGUCUCCAGAUGUUAAUUUACUUUCUGCACCCCAAUUGGGAAUGCAAUAUUGGAUGAAAAGAGAGGUUUCUGGUAUUCACAGAAAGCUAGAUAUGCCUUAAAACAUACUCUGCCGAUCUAAUUACAGCCUUAUUUUUGUAUGCCUUUUGGGCAUUCUCCUCAUGCUUAGAAAGUUCCAAAUGUUUAUAAAGGUAAAAUGGCAGUUUGAAGUCAAAUGUCACAUAGGCAAAGCAAUCAAGCACCAGGAAGUGUUUAUGAGGAAACAACACCCAAGAUGAAUUAUUUUUGAGACUGUCAGGAAGUAAAAUAAAUAGGAGCUUAAGAAAGAACAUUUUGCCUGAUUGAGAAGCACAACUGAAACCAGUAGCCGCUGGGGUGUUAAUGGUAGCAUUCUUCUUUUGGCAAUACAUUUGAUUUGUUCAUGAAUAUAUUAAUCAGCAUUAGAGAAAUGAAUUAUAACUAGACAUCUGCUGUUAUCACCAUAGUUUUGUUUAAUUUGCUUCCUUUUAAAUAAACCCAUUGGUGAAAGUCUUUUUUUUUCUCUUCUUUUAAAAUAAAUCAGAAUUGCCGUAUUGACCAGGAAAAGAUUAUGUAUGCACGUGCACCAGGGUUAGUUUUUAAAAGUACAUGGCUCCAUAAAAAUGCUGUAGAUUACAGAGUGAUAAAAUAUGCAGGUUUUUUUGUUUUUGUUUUUUCUGUUGUGUGUGUGUCUGUAUUUGUGUACAUGUGUGUCCUUGCACUCACACCCAAGGUGGAUUAAAAUACAGGCCUGCAAACUGGCCUGCACUUUAUCAUUUGGAUUUGUGCUGCUUAAUGCUCAGCGAAAAAUGUCUAGUAAAAUGAAUUAUGGUUGUCAGGAGAGAGGUUAUUUCGACUUUUGAACCAAUUGCACAUUUCUCAUUACCCAAGCUGUGGUGAGAUCCCAGGGGCUGUGGUGAACAAAUGAUGCUUUUAUAGAUGGUCCCUAGCUUACAAUGAUUCAAUUUACAAUGCUUCAAUUUAACAAUUUGUUGACUUACAAUGGGUUUAUCAGGAUGUAACCCAAUGCAUUUCAACUUACGAUAUUUUCAGUUUCGAAUGGGUUUAUCCAGAUGUAACCCCAUCGUAAAUGGCGGAGCAUCUGUACUUCCUUCCUCUGGCAGAGUUCCUUAGAGCCUGUGCCAAUUACUUGAAAGUUUCAUUCUCUGCCAUUUACAUGUGUGCUAUUAGUAGAACCAAAUUUCUAAGCUGUGGCGUGCUGAAAAUAAAAUGCUUAUGAAGCAAAAA